GAAUUCCACAAGGAAAUCAUCUCAGGAGGAAGGGCUCAUACUUGGAUCCAGAAAAUAUCAACAUAGCCAAAGAAAAACAAUCAAGACAUACCUCCAGGAGCUGUGUAACAGCAACCGGAAAGAGAAACAAUGGUGUGUUCCUAUGUGGGAUAUAAAGAGCCGGGGCUCAGGGGGCUCCACACCUGCACCUCCUUCUCACCUGCUCCUCUACCUGCUCCACCCUCAAUCCACCAGAACCAUGGGCUGCUGUGGCUGCUCCGGAGGCUGUGGCUCCAGCUGUGGAGGCUGUGACUCCAGCUGUGGGAGCUGUGGCUCUGGCUGCAGGGGCUGUGGCCCCAGCUGCUGUGCACCCGUCUACUGCUGCAAGCCCGUGUGCUGCUGUGUUCCAGCCUGUUCCUGCUCUAGCUGUGGCAAGCGGGGCUGUGGCUCCUGUGGGGGCUCCAAGGGAGGCUGUGGUUCUUGUGGCUGCUCCCAGUGCAGUUGCUGCAAGCCCUGCUGUUGCUCUUCAGGCUGUGGGUCAUCCUGCUGCCAGUGCAGCUGCUGCAAGCCCUACUGCUCCCAGUGCAGCUGCUGUAAGCCCUGUUGCUCCUCCUCGGGUCGUGGGUCAUCCUGCUGCCAAUCCAGCUGCUGCAAGCCCUGCUGCUCAUCCUCAGGCUGUGGGUCAUCCUGCUGCCAGUCCAGCUGCUGCAAGCCCUGCUGCUCCCAGUCCAGAUGCUGUGUCCCUGUGUGCUACCAGUGCAAGAUCUGAGGCUCUAGUGGGAAACCUCAGGUAGCUCCUGAAGAUCUGUGCUUUCCAACAAGUGACUACCCUUGAAGCACAUCCCCUUCUGGAUCUGAAAAGAGCCCUUGGCUCAGGGCGUCUUUUUCCAGCCCCUGAGGAAAUGGAAUGAACCACUCCCUGCCCAUUCCCUAUAAGAAUAUCCCAAGACCCAGGCAAUUUUGCCCCUCUUUCCCACAUGCCCCCAUAUGUCUGAGCCAAACUGCACUGGGGGCUGCCCUCAUGCCAAGCAAGAGCCUGGAAUUCCCCUUCUUGAUAAUUCCAUGGGAGACAGCAAACCCUUCUUUCCUUUGCCUGCCAGGAGCUUCACGACAUUUGCAGAUGGAUGUCCUGCAACCCAAAUGAUCACAUGUAUCUAUGGAAAUCCAAAAUGCAUCUGGGUGCAGCACUAAAUAAAUUCUCCAUCCCUCA